AGACGGAAUCUCGCCCUUGUGCCAGGCUGGAGUGCAGUGGCACGAUCUCAGCUCACUGCAACCUCCGCCUUACUGGUUUAAGUGAUUCUCCUACCUCAGCCUUCCGAGUAGCUUGGAUUACAGGCAUGCGCCACCAUGCCCAGCUAAUUUUUGUAUUUUUAGUAGAGAUGGGGUUUCACCAUGUUGGCCAGGAUGGUCUCGAUCUCCUGACUUCGUGAUCUACCAGCCUUGGCCUCCCAAAGUGCUGGGAUUAGAGGCAUGAGCCACCGCACCCAGCUGAAACUCGUACUGUGUUUUAAGUGUUAUAACAUUGAGGAAUUUGAGGCAGUGGUGUGUGGUCUAAUAACAGAGCAUGAGAGAGCUUCAGCUUUGAUACUUAAUUUCUAUAUAUCCCAUCUUAUUCCGAAAGGAAUUUCAGUUAGCUUAAUUUCCAUUUUAGUGCUGUUUCUUUUUGUGUUAAUUUAUUGUUUUCUUAAUUGUGCUGAUUUAAAAUCCAGCCAACAAAUUAAUUUAACGCUUGUCUGUCUAAAUGUAUUUUCACUUCAAAGUCUCUUCAGUGAAUAUGAAGACAAUUAGCUAUAUUUUUGCUAACAAGAUUUGCUGAUGGGGAGAAGAGCGAGAUAAAGGAACAAAUCAAGGAUGAGUGUUAGGUUUUUGGCUUGAACUACUGUUGAAUGGUGGUGGUUUUUGGCUUGAACUGCUGUUGAAUGGUGGUGCUAUUUGGGCAUGUUUGUGAUGCCCAUUACACAUCCAGUGGACAGGCCAAUAGACAGCUCUUUGACUCUGGAGAGAUUUAACAAACUUUAAACAUUCUCAGGAGCUUAGAUGAACAAUGAACUGUUCCACUCUUUUAAGAACUUGAAUCUUGACACACAAGUGGGUAUCUUAAAGUCACAUUGCAUGUGAUUUUGGAGGCUUUUGAGAAUCCAUUUAUUGAUUUAGGAUUAGGGGAAUACAAAUUUAGUGUUUUAGGAAAUUGUUUAAAGCAAAGUGAAUAUUAAACUCGAAUUUUGUUUGUAUCAAAAAUUCUAAGUAUUAAAAAUGUUUCUCUGACUUGUCUGAGAAGGCUCAGUAAAUAAUUCUUCAAUUUGUAAUGAGAGUUUUGCUUUGCAUUAGCUAUUGGUCUAUAAAGUCCAGUAAGAUAGUCUAAUCUCUGCCUUCAGUUUUAUAGAUUAGUGGACGAGACAGACAAGUACUGAAAUACUUAAGAAAUACUUUUCACAAGUGGCAAUAGAACAAUGUGUUAUGGACUCAUUGCAGAAGGCUGAGGAGCAGUAAAGGAGGGAAGGUUCAAGAAAGCCUUCAAAAAGGAAAUAACACUUUAGCCAGAGCCCUACUCACCAGUAAGAGCAAAAAUUGUGCAACUUUGAUAUUUAAGAAAUGGAGGGUUACUGCUAGUCAUAGUGGUGGUGAGUAAUUCUAUAUGACUAAAGCAUCAAACUCUAAUAAGAGCAUUAUAAAAAGAGGCUAGAAAAUUGGACAGGCAACAUUCAACAUAUCUUAUAAUUAAAGAUUUGGUAGUUUAUGUUAGAGGUGAUAGACACAUAGGAGAGUUUUUAAAUGUGGGAGUAAAAUGGUCAGACUUGACUUUUUAGAACAGUAAUAAAGGAGUGCAGUUAUUUUUGGAAUUCAUUUAUGUGACUUUUUAAAGACUUCUGGGGUAGGCUGGUGCAGUGGCUUAUGGCUGUAAUCCCAUCACUUUGGGAGGCUAAGGUGGGCAGAUGGCUUCAGUCCAGGAGUUCGAGACCAGCCUGGACAACGUGGCGAAACCCCAUCUCUACAAAAAAUACAAUUAGCCAGGCGUGGCGGUGCGUGCCUAUAGUCCCAGCUACUCGCUAAGGGACGCUGAGGUGGGAGAAUCACCUGAGCCCAGGAGUUUAAGACUGCAGUGAGCUGUGAUUGCACCACUGCAUUCCAGCCUGGGCAACAGAGUGAGUCCCUGUCUCAAUAAAGAUCUUUAGGGUAGACUUAAUUGCAAAUGCUUUCUUAAAGGAUUUGUUUGUUUUCUUAGCUUUUUUUUAAAAAGUCACACGAUAAAGGGUGUGGUGGGUACCUAUAACUUAAUACGGACAUCAUUUAGCUAUAUUUUUGCCCAGUUAAUACAGUAAAUGAUUAAAAAUUCUUUCUUGCUUUAGGAUUAUAUGAAAUAAUUAAAUUAUAUAAUAAAUGAAUUAUUUUAUUAAUGUUUAGUGCUAUUCUCAUACAGUCUAUGAAUAAGGUUUCUUAGUAUAUUAUGUUUCUCAAUAAUACAGAAUUUUUUUGUUUCUUUCUUAGUAAUAGCUUCAUCAGAGACAAUAGAAUAGUGGUCGGGAAGUUAAAAUGAAAUUAUAUGUGUAGAUAAUUCUGUUUCAUAGAGUUUAAAUGAACUUUGGUGCUACUUCUAUUCAGGAACUAUUUAGACAUUAAUGUUGAUGUGUUAAAAAAAAAAAAAAACCUGCUCUAGGCCAAAUCAGAUCUUAAUCUGGUGGUAAUUUUGUACCCACAGAGUUUAUUGUUUAACAGGGCAAAUUAGAUGUAUUCUCUUUAUAUAUUUAUCAUAAGAGUAAGAAAUGUAAGUGUUCUAAAAGUACAUAUAAAGGUAAAACAAUUCAGAGGGGAAGAUUAUGUCUGGAGGAAGGGCAUCAGAAACUCUGUAGGAGCUAGGGCUUAAAAUUAAAAGAUAAGUAAGCUUUGGAGGUGUGCAAGUGGGGAGACCACCAACAAGCAAAGAAAAAGCAUACACAAAGACACAGAAAAAUGAUUAUCAUGGGAUUUUUUUUAAAGUAGAAUCUUAGCAACUUUUAAAAAGACAAAUUAUCAGGCAAUUACCACCUCAGACCUACUGAAUCAGAAACUACUGGGAUGAGGCCCAGCAAUGUGGCCCUCCAGGUGAUUCUGAAGCACACUCAAAUUUGACAAACUGCUUUGCAAUUUCAGGCAGAUAAAUUGACCUGGAAUAUGCAACUCUUUCUGAUCUUUGAUCUAGGAAAGGUUUUAAAGAAAUAAAUCUGAAGUAACAACAUUUAAAGAGUUCCAGUAAUUAGUUCAAUAAUAAUAGUUAACAUUUAUUGAGCCAUUUUAUGUACUAGACCUUUUGCUGAGUAAAGGUUAUUAUCUCAGUUUUAUAGAUGAGACACAGAGAGGUUAAAUAUGUUAAUUGUCACACAGCUAAGAAAGUACCAGAUCCAGAAUUUUAAUUUAUGUAGCUUACUAUAAAGCUGACAUUUUUUGGUGGGAAAUAAGUUCCAACUUGUAGAUACCUUUUUAAAGUACAAAACAAAGUUUUUACUUGUUUUAUGGACCACUUUUGUAUCUCUGAUGGGCAUGAAAAUUGCUAAGAACACUAUUGUAGAUUUUUAUUUUAAUAGAGCAUUCUCCAUUUUAAACUUUAAUUAUAGAAAGCAUUUUAAGAAAUGGCAUGCUAGGCUUUAAGAAAACUGGAUAAAUGAAAAUCCAAACUUAAAUAAGAUAAAUAUUUGGACGCAAAAGUUCUCAAGGUUCAUUAUGAGAAAUGUAGUCAUUUCACAUAAAAGCUUUGUUUUGCACAUUUCUCAAUAAUGUAAUUUGUCAUGUAAAAGAAGAAAAGUCUGGAGUGGGCCAGGCAUGGUGGCUUACACUUGUAUUCCCCAGCACUUUGGAAUGUUGAGGCAGGAGGAUUGCUGGAGCCCAGGAGUUCGAGACCAGCCUCCGCAACAUACAUGGGGAGACCCCAGCCCUACAAAAAAUAGUAAUAAUAAUUAGCUGGGCAUGGUGACAUGAGCCUGUGGUUCCAGCCACUUUGGAGGCUGAGGCAGGAGGAUCAUUUGAACAUGGGAGUUUGAAGCUAUGGUGAGCCAUGAUCAUGCCACUGCAUUCCAGUUUAGACAACAGAGUGAGACUCCGUCUGUGAAUGAGUGAAUGAAUGAAUGAAAAAGAAAAAGCUUAGAGUGAUUGUACCAGGCAUUCCUGAGGUACAUUCACAUUUUAUAAUUAAACUCAACCACUCUUUGUACUAAAUUUUUUCUCGCUGACAUUGACCUAAGAUAUAUUCCUUUCCCCUCUGUGUUUCUGCAACUAUUUAAGUUGAUAUCCUUCUCUAAGUCAGAUUCAAAAUAAUAUUUUGAAAUGCACUGAUACUAUAAGUAUCUAAAAAUACAUCUUUUCAGAUGCUUAAUCUUUGAGCAGAGAAAAUACAAACAUUCUAAUUAAAUGUGCAAGAUGCGUAUAUAAGUAACCAUGAGGAUCUUUGUUAAUAUGGAGUAACGACAUCAUAAACAAUCUUUUCUACUGUCCUUUUUUAUUUACGUUCAAUUUUUUGAACAGGCAAUACAGUCAUACAAUCCAAAAGAUAUGAAAAGACAUAAUAGUAAUGUCUCAUUCUCAUCCGUUUCCCUUAGGUACCCAUUUCCCUUCCCCACAGACACAUACUUUGUUAAUAGUUUUUCUUCCAGAGAUGAUAUAUGCAUAUGUACAAGCAAAUGCAAAUGUUUUUAUUUCUUUUUAACACCAGUAGUAAUAUAUUACAUAUAUACAUACUGCACUGUGUAUAUAAUGUACACUAUUGUUUCCUGCUUUUUACAUUUAUACUUAAUAUGUAUUUUUCAGAUACUGUCAUCUUACUAUAUAUAAAAAGCUAACUCAUUUGUUUUUCAGCUCUCUCAUAUUUGAUGGUAUGAAUAAAACAAAUUUAGCCAGUUUUGUAUUAAGAGGUUUCUUUGAUUGUAGUUUUUUGCUGUUACUAACAAUGCUGCAGUGGUUGGGCGCGUGGCUCACACCUGUAAUCUCAGCACUUUGGAAGGCUGAGGCGGGUGGAUCACCUAAGGUCAGGAGUUCAAGACCAGCCUGGAUAACAUAGUGAAACGCUGUCUCUACUAAAAAUAUGAAAAUUAGCUGGACCUGGUGGCACGCAUCUGUAAUUCCAGCUACUCAGGAGGCUGAGGCACAAGAAUUGCUUGAACCUGGGAAGCCGAGGUUGCAGUGGGCCGAGAUCGCACCACUGCACUCCAGCCUGGGCAACAGAGUGAGAUCCUGUCUCAAAACAAACAAACAAAGUGCUGUGCGGUUAAGAAGAUUGUCUACCAAAUAUAGAACAGAAAAGAUAUAUCCCACAGCCACUGGAGAAAAAGAAGAAAAUGUUAAAAAGAACAGAUACAAGGACAUACUGCCAUUUGAUCACAGCCGAGUUAAAUUGACAUUAAAGACUCCUUCACAAGAUUCAGACUAUAUCAAUGCAAAUUUUAUAAAGGGCGUCUAUGGGCCAAAAGCAUAUGUAGCAACUCAAGGACCUUUAGCAAAUACAGUAAUAGAUUUUUGGAGGAUGAUAUGGGAGUAUAAUGUUGUGAUCAUUGUAAUGGCCUGCCGAGAAUUUGAGAUGGGAAGGAAAAAAUGUGAGCGCUAUUGGCCUUUGUAUGGAGAAGACCCCAUAACGUUUGCACCAUUUAAAAUUUCUUGUGAGGAUGAACAAGCAAGAACAGACUACUUCAUCAGGACACUCUUACUUGAAUUUCAAAAUGAAUCUCGUAGGCUGUAUCAGUUUCAUUAUGUGAACUGGCCAGACCAUGAUGUUCCUUCAUCAUUUGAUUCUAUUCUGGACAUGAUAAGCUUAAUGAGGAAAUAUCAAGAACAUGAAGAUGUUCCUAUUUGUAUUCAUUGCAGUGCAGGCUGUGGAAGAACAGGUGCCAUUUGUGCCAUAGAUUAUACGUGGAAUUUACUAAAAGCUGGGAAAAUACCAGAGGAAUUUAAUGUAUUUAAUUUAAUACAAGAAAUGAGAACACAAAGGCAUUCUGCAGUACAAACAAAGGAGCAAUAUGAACUUGUUCAUAGAGCUAUUGCCCAACUGUUUGAAAAACAGCUACAACUAUAUGAAAUUCAUGGAGCUCAGAAAAUUGCUGAUGGAGUGAAUGAAAUUAACACUGAAAACAUGGUCAGCUCCAUAGAGCCUGAAAAACAAGAUUCUCCUCCUCCAAAACCACCAAGGACCCGCAGUUGCCUUGUUGAAGGGGAUGCUAAAGAAGAAAUACUGCAGCCACCGGAACCUCAUCCAGUGCCACCCAUCUUGACACCUUCUCCCCCUUCAGCUUUUCCAACAGUCACUACUGUGUGGCAGGACAAUGAUAGAUACCAUCCAAAGCCAGUGUUGCAUAUGGUUUCAUCAGAACAACAUUCAGCAGACCUCAACAGAAACUAUAGUAAAUCAACAGAACUUCCAGGGAAAAAUGAAUCAACAAUUGAACAGAUAGAUAAAAAAUUGGAACGAAAUUUAAGUUUUGAGAUUAAGAAGGUCCCUCUCCAAGAGGGACCAAAAAGUUUUGAUGGGAACACACUUUUGAAUAGGGGACAUGCAAUUAAAAUUAAAUCUGCUUCACCUUGUAUAGCUGAUAAAAUCUCUAAGCCACAGGAAUUAAGUUCAGAUCUAAAUGUCGGUGAUACUUCCCAGAAUUCUUGUGUGGACUGCAGUGUAACACAAUCAAACAAAGUUUCAGUUACUCCACCAGAAGAAUCCCAGAAUUCAGACACACCUCCAAGGCCAGACCGCUUGCCUCUUGAUGAGAAAGGACAUGUAACGUGGUCAUUUCAUGGACCUGAAAAUGCCAUACCCAUACCUGAUUUAUCUGAAGGCAAUUCCUCAGAUAUCAACUAUCAAACUAGGAAAACUGUGAGUUUAACACCAAGUCCUACAACACAAGUUGAAACACCUGAUCUUGUGGAUCAUGAUAACACUUCACCACUCUUCAGAACACCCCUCAGUUUUACUAAUCCACUUCACUCUGAUGACUCAGACUCAGAUGAAAGAAACUCUGAUGGUGCUGUGACCCAGAAUAAAACUAAUAUUUCAACAGCAAGUGCCACAGUUUCUGCUGCCACUAGUACUGAAAGCAUUUCUACUAGGAAAGUAUUGCCAAUGUCCAUUGCUAGACAUAAUAUAGCAGGAACAACACAUUCAGGUGCUGAAAAAGAUGUUGAUGUUAGUGAAGAUUCACCUCCUCCCCUACCUGAAAGAACUCCUGAAUCGUUUGUGUUAGCAAGUGAACAUAAUACACCUGUAAGAUCGGAAUGGAGUGAACUUCAAAGUCAGGAACGAUCUGAACAAAAAAAGUCUGAAGGCUUGAUAACCUCUGAAAAUGAGAAAUGUGAUCAUCCAGCGGGAGGUAUUCACUAUGAAAUGUGCAUAGAAUGUCCACCUACUUUCAGUGACAAGAGAGAACAAAUAUCAGAAAAUCCAACAGAAGCCACAGAUAUUGGUUUUGGUAAUCGAUGUGGAAAACCCAAAGGACCAAGAGAUCCACCUUCAGAAUGGACAUGAUUCAGGGAGCUAGAAGACACUUUAAGUUAUACUGGAAAAUUCAGGUGCCACUGAAAGCCAGAUUUAUAGUAUUCCAUCUUUAAUAUGUGGGACUAACAGCAGUGUAGAUUGUUACCUUAAUAUUUUUUGCUGGGACCAUCUACCUGCCUUAUACUACACUUAGGAAAAAGUAUUACAUAUGGUUUAUUUUGAAACUUCAAGUAUUAUUGCCUUAAUGUCUCUUAACCCUGUUACACGCUGCUUGUAGACAUGUUAAUAUAGUAAUACCUUUAUGAUAUAUUGAGUUUAAGGACUACUCUUUUUCUGUUUUAUCAUGUAUGCAUUAUUUUGUAUAUGUACAGGGCAAGUAGGUAUAUAAUUUGAUAAAGUUGCAAUUGAAAUAUUAUUAACAGAAGAUGUAAGAAAUUUCUGCAUGGUCUAAAUCUUUGUGUACUUUAUUUGUAAAUUAUUUGCCCUGGAGUUUUAGAAAAUAGUUUCUGAAUUUUAAACUUGCUGGAUUCAUGCAGCCAGCUUUGCAGGUUAUCAGAGAUCAAAGAUUGUAAUAAUAAUUUUGUAAAUUGUAAGCAAAAAGUUAUUUUUAUAUUAUAUACAGUCUAAUUGUUCAUCCUAAUUGUUCCUGUUUUCAUCUAGUCAGAGAUUCAGUAAGUGCCUUGGAACAAUAUUGAAUUCUCUUAGCUUGUGUGUGUUUCUUUAAUAUUUGAACUCAAGUGGGAUUAGAAGACUAUCAAAAUACAUGUAUGUUUCAGGAUAUUUGACCUGUCAUUAAAAAAAACAAACAGUUUUACAGUG